GUUGCUAGGUAACCACAUCUCCCAUAACUGCCCCAGCACAUCGUCCUGAGCCGCCCAACCUGUCUCCAGCCACCUUCUGUGGAGUCUCAAACUCCAUCAUCUGUGGGACCCUGUAGGCCGAAGGGAGAAACAAGAGUGCAGCCACCACCCCUGAGCCACCUGUGGCUCUGCUACCCACAAUUUCACUGUGAAGAGUCAGCUGCCUGGGCCGUGAGGUCACUGCCACCAUGAGUCUGGGCAUCAUGGAAGAGGAAGACCUGGCCGAGUACUUCCGGCUGCAGUAUGGGGAGCGGCUGCUGCAGAUGCUCCAGAAACUCCCCAAUGUUGAGGGGGCGUCGGAGUCCCCAUCCAUCUGGCUACUGGAGAAGAAAAAGGAGACAGAAAUCAUGCAUCAAACUAUGGUGCAGAAGAAGAAGAUGUUUCAGCGCAGAAUGGAAACCCUGAACCUGCGCUGGGAGGAACUGGGCGUUAAGGAAGCCCAACUGAAGGCUCACAUCCAGAAGUCUGAGCAGUUCAUCCAGGAGAACGACCAGAAACGGAUCCGCGCCAUGAAGAAAGCCAACAAGGAGCGAGAACUCAAGUGCCAGCACAUGCAGGAGCUGACCAAGCGCAAGCAGGAGAUGGUGGCGCUGCGGCUGGAGCACCAGCGGCUGAGCGCCAAGCUGAAGGACUACUACAUCUUCAACAAGUACCUAGAGAAGGUGGUGGAGAACUCCGAGUUCGAGGAGAUCCAUGAGGUGAUUGCACGCUACAAGACGCUGGUGAGCAUGCGCCACGACCUCAUGCAGUCUGCGCAGGAAGGCCAGGAGAAGAUUGAGCGCGCCAAGGCCCGGCUGGCGCGCUACAUGGAGGAAAAGGAUGAUGAGAUCCUGCAGCAAAACAAUGAGCUGGCAAGGCUGCAGAUGCGCUUUGACCGUGCCCGCAGCAAUGUCAUCUUCUGGGAAUCUCGCUGGGCGCACAUCCAGAACACCGCAGCCAAGAAGACCCUCCUGCUUGGCACCAUUAAGAUGGCCACGCUGAACCUCUUCCAGAUCGUGAGCAAGCACCUGAAGGAGGUGACUGAGGUGGCACUGGAGGACACCCACAAGCAGCUGGACAUGAUCCAGCAAUUUAUCCAAGACCGGUCGGACAUCUGGGCAGAGGUGAAAAAGAAGGAACAACAGCGAGUCCGGAUUUAAGGAGGCAGCCUUGUUCCAGAAUGUCCUGAGACAGAGAUCGUGAAAGAAGAAGUCGUGAGCCUGCGGUCCAGUCAGUCCAGCUCGGGACCGAUGCCUGCUGUGCCUUCCUGCUGAGGGACACCUGCUUAUUUUCCCCCGUGGGCCUCACUCUAUCCCUGAAAACAGUGAAUGUUAUAUGAAGUUUGUUCUCAAGUU